CUCCCUUCUGCCUGGGACGUCAGCGGACGGGGCGCUCGCGGGCCGGGGCUGUAUGGGGCUCCCGCGCGGGUCGUUCUUCUGGCUGCUGCUCCUGCUCACGGCUGCCUGCUCGGGGCUCCUCUUUGCCCUGUACUUCUCGGCGGUGCAGCGGUACCCGGGGCCAGCGGCCGGAGCCAGGGACACCACAUCAUUUGAAGCAUUCUUUCAAUCCAAGGCAUCGAAUUCUUGGACAGGAAAGGGCCAGGCCUGCCGACACCUGCUUCACCUGGCCAUUCAGCGGCACCCCCACUUCCGUGGCCUGUUCAAUCUCUCCAUUCCAGUGCUGCUGUGGGGGGACCUCUUCACCCCAGCGCUCUGGGACCGCCUGAGCCAACACAAAGCCCCGUAUGGCUGGCGGGGGCUCUCUCACCAAGUCAUCGCCUCCACCCUGAGCCUUCUGAACGGCUCAGAGAGUGCCAAGCUGUUUGCCCCGCCCAGGGACACCCCUCCAAAGUGUAUCCGGUGUGCCGUGGUGGGCAACGGAGGCAUUCUGAAUGGGUCCCGCCAGGGUCCCAACAUCGAUGCCCAUGACUAUGUAUUCAGACUCAAUGGAGCUGUGAUCAAAGGCUUCGAGCGCGAUGUGGGCACCAAGACUUCCUUCUAUGGUUUCACUGUGAACACGAUGAAGAACUCCCUCGUCUCCUACUGGAAUCUGGGCUUCACCUCCGUGCCACAAGGACAGGACCUGCAGUAUAUCUUCAUCCCCUCAGACAUCCGCGACUAUGUGAUGCUGAGAUCGGCCAUUCUGGGCGUGCCUGUCCCUGAGGGCCUAGAUAAAGGGGACAGGCCGCACGCCUAUUUUGGACCAGAAGCCUCUGCCAGUAAAUUCAAGCUGCUACAUCCGGACUUCAUCAGCUACCUGACAGAAAGGUUCUUGAAAUCAAAGUUGAUUAACACACAUUUUGGAGACCUAUAUAUGCCUAGUACCGGGGCUCUCAUGCUGCUGACAGCUUUGCAUACCUGUGACCAGGUCAGUGCCUAUGGAUUCAUCACAAGCAACUACUGGAAAUUUUCCGACCACUAUUUCGAACGAAAAAUGAAGCCAUUGAUAUUUUAUGCAAACCACGAUCUGUCCCUGGAAGCUGCCCUGUGGAGGGACCUGCACAAGGCCGGCAUCCUUCAGCUGUACCAGCGCUGACCCCAAUGCACUGAGCCCUUUGCUUCUUCAAGAGUUGCGGCCCUGAUCCUCUCAAGUGGCCAAAAGCUUUUUUAACUUUUCAAUCUUCACCUUCCCUUGCCAACAGAGGGCACUGGGGUGAAUUCAAGAUUUUCAUCGAGGUCUGUUCAAUAUAGGACACCCCAGCUUGUCCUUGGCUCAUCCAAGAACUCUUCUGUAUCUAAAACAAUACAUCUCAAUCUUGGCCAAGGGAAAAUGGACUGCUUUGCUGGAUUGGCACUGAGCAACUUUAGGAAAUGUCGGUGGAGUGUUCAGCAAGAUCAGACAGCAGUCCAGGUCAAAGGCAAACACACACGCUCCAGCCCAAAUCCUCCUGGUGGCACAUCCUACCCCAGAUGCUAAAGUGAUUCAAGGACUCCAGGACACCUCUUAAGAGCCUUUCUAAGAACAUGAUAGGCUUACUUCUGCUCCAUAAUAAAGUGGGAGAAAAAAGCCAGAAUAUAACUUAAGACUAGAUAACUGCGUACAUGAUGGACCAUUUUUUUUUUUUUGGCUGGGUAGAGAAAUCAUAUAAAACGCAGGCUGUUUAGCAUGGAGAUGACUCUCAGAACACUGGGAGGGUCUGGCACUUGAUGGGGGUUAGUUGCUUGGCAGCCUGCCUGCCACUGAGGGAAGUCCCAUUAGAGAUGUAUCACCACCUUGUCACCAACAGGAUGAUGUCACCAGGUAAUAAACCUUCAUCCUCAUA